ACAGUGAGACUAGCAUUCACUGCUGGCCAGUGCCUGCCUUUUUCACCACCUCUAAUUUCAGCUUCAGCAGUUGCUUGGAACUUUGGUUCUGGCAGCAGCAGCAACAUCAUUACCGCUAGCGGCAGUUUUGUGCCGAGGCACCUACACACCUCCCGUCCUCUCUGCCAGAUCGCGGGCCUGUCGGUGUCUGCUCCUACACGCCAACGCCGGUGGGCAGGACCAUGUCUCUGGUAAGCCAGAAUUCGCGCCGCCGCCGCCGCCGCGUUGCAAAGGCUACUGCGCACAACAGCAGCUGGGGCGAAAUGCAGGCCCCUAAUGCCCCCGGUCUCCCCGCUGAUGUGCCAGGCUCAGACGUCCCCCAGGGUCCCAGCGAUUCCCAGAUCCUCCAGGGCCUCUGCGCCUCUGAGGGCCCAAGCACCUCCGUUCUGCCCACCUCCGCUGAGGGCCCAAGCACCUUUGUGCCGCCCACCAUCUCUGAGGCCUCAAGCGCCUCCGGGCAGCCCACCAUCUCUGAGGGACCUGGCACCUCCGUGCUGCCCACCCCCAGUGAGGGCCUAAGCACCUCCGGGCCUCCCACCAUCUCUAAGGGGCUGUGCACCUCUGUGACGCUUGCCGCCUCUGAGGGCCGGAACACCUCCAGGCCGCCCACUUCCUCUGAGGAACCUAGCACCUCCGUGCCGCCCACCGCCUCUGAGGUACCGAGCACCUCCCUGCCGCCCACCCCUGGUGAGGGAACGAGCACCUCCGUGCCGCCCACAGCCUAUGAGGGACCAAGCACCUCCGUGGUGCCCACCCCUGAUGAGGGACCAAGCACCUCCGUGCUGCCUACACCUGGUGAGGGACCAGGCACCUCCGUGCCGCUCGCCGCCACUGAGGGCCUGAGCACCUCCGUGCAGGCCACUCCUGAUGAGGGACCGAGCACCUCCGUGCCGCCCACCGCCACUGAGGGCCUAAGCACCCCCGUGCCACCCACCCGUGAUGAGGGACCGAGCACCUCCGUGCCGGCCACUCCUGGUGAGGGACCGAGCACCUCCGUGCUGCCCGCCGCCUCUGACGGACAAAGCAUCUCCUUGGUGCCCACCCGCGGUAAGGGAUCAAGCACCUCCGUGCCCCCCACCGCCACCGAGGGCCUGAGCACCUCCGUGCAGCCCACUGCUGGUGAGGGAUCGAGCACCUCCGUGCCGCCCACCCCUGGUGGGGGACUGAGCACCUCCGUGCCGCCCACCGCCACUGAGGAGUUGAGCACCUCCGUGCCGCCCACUCCCGGUGAGGGACCAAGCACUUCCGUACUGCCAAUCCCCGGUGAGGGACUGAGCACCUCUGUGCCGCCCACCGCCUCUGAUGGAUCGGACACCUCCGUGCCGCCCACUCCUGGUGAGGGCGCAAGCACCUUAGUGCAGCCCACCGCCCCUGACGGACCGGGAAGCUCCGUGCUGCCUAACCCUGGUGAGGGCCCGAGCACAUUGUUUAGCUCUAGUGCUUCUGUGGACCGGAACCCCUCCAAGUGUUCCCUUGUUUUGCCAAGCCCUAGGGUAACCAAGGCCUCCGUGGACUCAGAUUCUGAGGGUCCUAAGGGUGCAGAAGGCCCUAUAGAAUUCGAGGUCCUGAGAGACUGUGAGAGCCCCAACUCCAUUAGUAUUAUGGGCCUCAAUACUUCCCGGGUUGCAAUUACCCUGAAGCCCCAAGACCCUAUGGAACAGAACGUAGCUGAGCUGUUGCAGUUCCUGCUGGUGAAGGAUCAGAGCAAGUACCCUAUCCGGGAGUCUGAAAUGCGGGAAUAUAUUGUUAAAGAAUAUCGCAACCAGUUUCCUGAGAUACUCAGGCGAGCAGCAGCCCACCUGGAGUGCAUUUUUAGGUUUGAAUUGAGAGAACUUGACCCUGAGGCACACACCUACAUUCUGUUAAACAAACUGGGACCUGUGCCCUUUGAAGGGUUAGAAGAGAGCCCAAAUGGGCCAAAGAUGGGCCUCCUGAUGAUGAUUCUAGGCCAAAUAUUCCUGAAUGGCAACCAAGCCAAGGAGGCUGAGAUUUGGGAAAUGCUCUGGAGGAUGGGGGUGCAGCGGGAAAGGAGGCUUUCCAUUUUUGGGAACCCAAAGAGACUUCUGUCUGUGGAGUUUGUAUGGCAGCGUUACUUAGACUACAGGCCAGUAACUGACUGUAAACCAGUGGAGUAUGAGUUUUUCUGGGGCCCAAGAUCCCACCUAGAAACCACCAAGAUGAAAAUUCUGAAGUUCAUGGCGAAAAUAUAUAACAAAGAUCCUAUGGAUUGGCCAGAGAAAUACAACGAAGCUCUGGAAGAAGAUGCUGCCAGAGCCUUUGCUGAGGGUUGGCAGGCUCUCCCUCACUUUAGGAGGCCCUUUUUUGAGGAAGCUGCUGCAGAGGUACCAUCCCCUGAUUCAGAGGUUUCCAGCUAUUCCUCAAAAUAUGCCCCACAUUCAUGGCCUGAGUCAAGAUUGGAGAGCAAGGCAAGGAAGCUGGUGCAGUUAUUUCUGCUUAUGGAUUCAACUAAGCUGCCUAUACCAAAGAAAGGAAUUCUGUACUACAUUGGCCGAGAGUGCAGCAAAGUGUUCCCUGACCUCCUGAAUCGUGCUGCCCGCACCCUGAACCAUGUCUAUGGGACAGAACUAGUGGUACUUGAUCCCAGGAAUCACUCCUAUACUCUGUACAACCGAAGGGAGAUGGAAGAAACUGAGGAGAUCGUAGACAGUCCAAACAGGCCUGGCAACAACUUUUUGAUGCAGGUCCUAAGCUUCAUCUUUAUUAUGGGCAACCAUGCCAGGGAGUCUGCAGUCUGGGCCUUUCUGCGGGGCUUAGGGGUUCAAGCUGGGAGAAAGCAUGUGAUUACCUGCAGAUACUUGAGUCAGCGCUAUAUAGACAGUUUACGGGUUCCUGACAGUGAUCCAGUGCAAUAUGAGUUUGUAUGGGGUCCUAGAGCCCGUUUGGAAACCUCUAAGAUGAAAGCCUUGCGAUAUGUGGCCAGAAUCCACAGAAAGGAACCACAGGACUGGCCACAGCAGUACAGGGAGGCAAUGGAAGAUGAGGCCAAUAGAGCUGAUGUUGGGCACAGGCAAAUCUUUGUUCACAACUUCAGGUAGAGGAAUGCAUGGCAGUCAGAGGGGCCUUGCAAGGAGGGGCCUUUGAGCCUCAGUUCUCAUGUAUUGGGGGGUGGGGGUGGGUACAUAUUGUAUUUGGUAUUUGUGUUCCAGUUAUAUUUAUGUCUUUUCAUAUUUAGUUCUGGUGUGGUGUCUGGAAAUGUUUCAACUGUUUUAAUAUAUUGUCUGAUUGGGUAAAUGUGAUUGACCACUUGCUGUCUCUGUUGUAUUUUGGUAUGAGUUUUGAUAGCUCUAUAAAAUGUUUUGGAAAUCUUUCCAUCUUGUUGCAUUAUCUAGAAAAGAAUAUAGCAUAUAGCUAUAGAUAUAGGCUUUUCCUUGAAAGCUUGAAAAAAAUUCGCCAGUAAAAUAAUCUAGCUUAAAGUGAUAAACUAACAAACAAAUAUAACAACAACUGAAAAGGCACUCUAAAUUGUGGCUGGCUUCCCUUUCUGUCUGCUAUUGUAUGAAGAAUACUGAUGUUUACCUGUAUUUGCUUUGCUGUACUAAAAUGUAAUGAAAAAUAAAAGAUUAAUAAAUGAAA